AGUGACCCUAGGCCUCUUGCAGGAGAGUCCCUGGUCCCAGCCAGCGGGAGCGGCUUCUCCAGUUUGUGGCUCUCGGAGAGUUCGCCUCGUCCCUCCCUCUCAGAUAACCACCUAUUUCUGACCUCUGGAGGCCGGGCUGAGCCCGGAAUUUUAUGACCAGCGCCCGCUGGCCGUCGUCACCCUCUAAUUUCUCGCAAAACUCCCGGGGACCCUUCUUAAUGUCAGUAGCCACAGUCGCCGCCGCUCCUGCGCCUAGAAGCCUUCCACGACCCUCAACCCCACAGAGCCCCGAGCAGGCUCGGGUUCCCGCAGGAUACACUGCCCGCCCAGUGGCCUGGAGGGCGCGUCCCGGGCUCCCCUACGCCUUUUGGAAUCAGCGACAGACGCAGGUAUAAAAGAGAGCCUCCACUCCCACCUCUCCAGGGCUCCCCACCCGCUCCUUCUGGCCGCUUUCUCCUGAAAGAGCAAGGCACCCCUAGAAGCUUCAGGCUCCUCCACAGGCGAGUGCCUACCCACCUAUCAGGUUCAUAGGUGGAAGAAAUUCAUCUCCAGAUGAGACUUUGGACUUGGACUUGGGACUUUUGAGUUAAUGCCAGAAUGAUGAACCCCAGCAUGUUAAUUGAACUUGAUCACCCAGUUGAAGGAAGAAUAAUAGUAGAUGUUGGAUCUUCAGGAAGCUGAAGAGGGCAGUGCCCAGAAAUACCUGUCUUGAUAGGGGGAUUUGAGCUGAACCAAAGCAUCAACACCAAUCAGACUGUUUCCGAAGAACUAGAGUUUUCUGGGUCAGCAAUGGAAAGCCUCAGAGGGAAUACUGCUCAGGGUCCUACAAAUGAAGAAGACUAUAAAAACGAAGGCCAAUUAUCAAGGCAAACAAAAUGUCCUGCACAGAAGAAAUCCUCUUUUGAGAACACAGUGGUCAGAAAAGUGUCAGUGACACUCAAAGAAAUUUUCACAGGGGAGGAAGGCCCUGAAUCCAGUGAAUUUAGUCUAAGCCCAAACCUUGACGCACAACAGAAAAUUCCAAAGGGACAUGGAUCCCCAAUAUCUAGGAAAAACUCCAAAGAUAAUUCAGACUUAAUUAAACACCAAAGACUUUUCUCACAAAGAAAACCUUGUAAAUGCAAUGAAUGUGAAAAAGCCUUUAGUUACCAAUCAGACCUUCUUGUACACAGUAGAAUUCAUGGUGGAGAAAAGCCUUUUGAAUGCAACAAAUGUGGGAAAUCUUUCAGCCGAAGUACACACCUUAUUGAACAUCAAAGAACUCACACUGGAGAGAAACCUUAUGAAUGCAAUGAAUGUGGAAAAGCUUUUAGCCGGAGCACACAUCUUAGUCUACAUCAGAGAAUCCAUACUGGAGAAAAACCAUAUGAAUGUAGUGAAUGUGGAAAAGCCUUUAGCCGAAGCACUAACCUUAGUCAGCAUCAGCGAACUCAUACUCAAGAAAGGCCUUACAAAUGUAAUGAAUGUGGGAAAGCCUUCGGUGACCGUUCAACCAUAAUUCAGCAUCAACGAAUACACACUGGAGAGAAUCCCUAUGAAUGCAGUAAAUGUGGAAAAGCUUUCAGUUGGAUCUCAUCGCUUACUGAACAUCAGAGAACACACACUGGGGAGAACCCCUAUGAGUGCAGUGAAUGUGGGAAAGUGUUCAGUCGAAGCUCGUCUCUUACAGAACAUCAGAGAAUCCACAGUGGAGAAAAGCCUCACGAGUGUAGAGUGUGUGGAAAGGGCUUCAGUCGAAGCUCAUCCCUUAUUAUUCAUCAGAGAACUCAUACCGGGGAGAAGCCGUACAAAUGUAAUGACUGUGGAAAAGCCUUCUGUCAGAGUUCAACUCUGAUCAGACAUCAGCACCUUCAUACUAAAGAGUAAUAUCUGAGCUUUUAUUAAUGUUAGCAUAAGAACACAUAUACCUAACCUCCCACCACUGAAAUAUAUAUAUUUCAAGUAUAUAUAUACUUGUUCUAAUUUUCUUUUAUUAGAUACCUAUACCCGUUUUAAGCUUUCAUUCGUUCUUUCCAUCCAUCUAUCCUUCUUUCGUCUCCCCUCCCUUCUUCCCUCCUUCCCUCCUUCCUACUUUUUCUCCCUCUCCCUGUUCUUUCUUUCUCUUUUCUCAAAUAAGUUCACAAUAAAACAAAGGGAUGACUCAAAAAACAUAACAUAUGAAAUCUAAUAUUCUGAAGGGCUCCAACUUUAGAGUAUAAAGCUAUCUGACACCUUGUAGUUUCUCUGCUAAUCUAUUCCUUCAAGCGUGGGUCCCCGAACCACCAGGUUCUCCUCUGUUUUCUAACCACAUCAGCCCCUGCACAUGAAGAGAAAAUCCUGUGUGUGUGUCUUCAUACUUGCUGGCUCUAGUACCAGAAGAGAGGGAUCUGGCUUCAGAGCAGGACUGAAAACUUCUCACCAGUCUGGGGAUAAUAGUGUUGAGGCAAAUUCAUUCUCUUGACUUGCAAAAACAGAUUUUUCUCAUCUUCCUCCUUCUCUCACCUUUUUUGCAGUAGCAUUUUUCCUCAAAGUACAACUCAUUUUUUUACUAACGCCUAACUAAUCCUAGUGUUAUUUUAUCAUAUUUUUACCAAGAAUGUUCUAAAAAUCUUGGAGACGUUCCUCCAUGAUCUUGGGAAAAAAAGUUGCCAAAUGCUGUGCUGUUUUUUUUGUUUGUUUUUAAUUUUCUUUCAUUUACAGAUUUCAUGAAACUUAUAUUCUGUGGCUUUGACCCUCACCAAUCUUGGAAGAUUGAUCUCUCAAGGACAAACCCAGUGCCUAUUUCUCAGUCCUUUUUCUACUUGACAUUUGCAGAAUUGGCACUUUUUGCCACUGUUAUGCCUUAAAUCUUGAGCUUCUUUCAGGAUCCAUGAUUCUGUGCUGAUCUACACUUUUCCUACCUCUCAGCAUUUCUUUGAUUGUCAAUGAUCAGCUCUGUGAUUUGGGGCAAGGGUUAGGCCAGAAUUAUCUCAUUUUAUCAAGUUAUAAAACUUGAGGUAGUGCAACUAGAUUAUACACUUCUUGAAGACAGAAAUCUUGGUUUGUUUGUUGUUUUAUUUUUGAGAGAAGGUCUUGCUGUGUUGCCCAGGCUGGAGUGCAAUGGCACAAUCAUAGCUCACUGUAGCCUUGAACUUCUGGGCUCCUGCCACAGCCUCCUGAGUAGCUAGGGCUGCAAGUGUGUACCACCACACCCACAAUUUUAAAGUUUUUUUGUGGAGACAGGAUCUCACUAUAUUGGCAAGGCUGGCCUCCAUCUCCUGAACUCAAACAAUUCUCCCACCUCGGCUUCCGAAAACACUGACAUUACAGGUGUGAGCCACCACACCUGCCAGAAAUCUUGUUUUUGAUUGAUAUAAAACAUCACAAAGUACUGAGUAGACACUAAAUGCUCUGUAAUUAUUGCUCACUGAUUCCUCUUUAUCUGUAAUCAAUCAACUUGACUUUAUUUGAUAUGGAUUAAUAAUUGAUUUCUUUCUCUCUUUCUACUGCUGCUUCCAAGUUCUUGGUACCUUGUGCCUAGAUUACUAAAUUGAUCACUGUUGACUCACUACCAUUAUCUAGCUCCUUACUAAACUACUACUUUGUUAAAAAAAAAUAGUCGUUUCCCAGUGACCUCUGCCCCAAAUGUAAACUUCUUUAACCUAAAGGUCUUUCAUAGUUUGAUCUACUUACUUACUUCCUUUCUCUUCUCAAAGAUAAUACAUGCGGGCAGGCCUGUUUUGUCCCUACUAUACCCUCUUCUCACACUUUUCUUCUUUUCAAACUGUUCCUUGGCACUUCUACAUGUCCUACUUUCUUCGUUGUAUUCCAGAAACCCUAUCCACCCUUUUUUAAAGGCCAUGCUCAUAUCCUGGCUCUGUGACACUUUCAGUCCCCUGCCUUCUUAGAAAUCCUUUGUAGUGAUGGUUUGCAUUAUUCUCCUGUAUUAGACACCUUCUUUACUGUUUUCUGGUUCUUUCACAAGUACUUUUUUACAUAAGCUGUUUUGAAGUUGUAAAUCAUCCUAAAUCUUUUAUAAGCCUCAUAUAAUACAUAGUACAAUGCCAGCCUGGACUCUAGUUUUAAUCUAAAUACAUAGGGUUUAAUUUAGCAGCAUAAUCUUUUUAGUCUUUUGAAUGAUGAGGUAACCUCAUAGGUAUUUUGGCCCAUUUUGUUUUUCCUUGAAUUACAUAUAUAACUGACUAUUUAGACUGACUCCUUUAGAUCUCCUGGGAUGCUGACCUCUUGGCUUUCCAAUUCAUGAGACUAUUGUAAAGAAUAAGUGAGUUCAUUCAUGUAAAGUAGUAAAACAGUGCCUGACAAAAGUAAAUGCUCAAUAAAUUCUAAUUGUUAUGAUUCUAGUGAUUCA